AGUUGUGGACGCUCGUAAGUUUUCGGCAGUUUCCGGGGAGACUCGGGGACUCCGCGUCUCGCUCUCUGUGUUCCAAUCGCCCGGUGCGGUGGUGCAGGGUCUCGGGCUAGUCAUGGCGUCCCCGUCUCGGAGACUGCAGACUAAACCAGUCAUUACUUGUUUCAAGAGCGUUCUGCUAAUCUACACUUUUAUUUUCUGGGUGAGAGACGAAGGCGCCUGGGGCCGGCAGGGGAUCCCGGGCUUUUAGUUGUGGGGGGUGUGACCCUGAGCGGCGGGAGCUCAGGUCGGGAACGGUGUGGGGUUUGGGCGGCCAUCGCGCCUGGGACCCCGACGCCGGCGACCAGUGACUGGGCCCCGAACAAAGAGCUCAGGCAUCUCGCCGGCGCUGGGGUCGGAGUGCGGGACGAAGGCAGCCGAGAGGCUGAGCUGGGACCCAGACGUACCAGCGUUCGAGUUCGAUACGGGAGGCGAGGUGGGGCCUUAAGCCCCCAGAGCACGCAGACGGUGACCCUGGACCUUUGCAAAGGCAAGCAAGGCUUGCCCGGCCCCUUUGAGGGCUCACUUGCAUAAUAGUGUCUUUCUUUUCACUGCUUCGUAAGAGAGGAGUGUUUCGCAGAUCACUGGCGUUAUCCUUCUUGCAGUUGGCAUUUGGGGCAAGGUGAGCCUGGAGAAUUACUUUUCUCUUUUAAAUGAGAAGGCCACCAAUGUCCCCUUCGUGCUCAUUGCUACUGGUACCGUCAUUAUUCUUUUGGGCACCUUUGGUUGUUUUGCUACCUGCCGAGCUUCUGCAUGGAUGCUAAAACUGUAUGCAAUGUUUCUGACUCUCGUUUUUUUGGUCGAACUGGUCGCUGCCAUCGUAGGAUUUGUUUUCAGACAUGAGAUUAAGAACAGCUUUAAGAAUAAUUAUGAGAAGGCUUUGAAGCAGUAUAACUCUACAGGAGAUUAUAGAAGCCAUGCAGUAGACAAGAUCCAAAAUACGUUGCAUUGUUGUGGUGUCACCGAUUAUAGAGAUUGGACAGAUACUAAUUAUUACUCAGAAAAAGGAUUUCCUAAGAGUUGCUGUAAACUUGAAGAUUGUACUCCACAGAGAGAUGCAGACAAAGUAAACAAUGAAGGUUGUUUUAUAAAGGUGAUGACCAUUAUAGAGUCAGAAAUGGGAGUCGUUGCAGGAAUUUCCUUUGGAGUUGCUUGCUUCCAACUGAUUGGAAUCUUUCUCGCCUACUGCCUCUCUCGUGCCAUAACAAAUAACCAGUAUGAGAUAGUGUAACCCAAUGUAUCUGUGGGCCUAUUCCUCUCUACCUUUAAGGACAUUUAGGGUCCCCCCUGUGAAUUAGAAAGUUGCUUGGCUGGAGAACUGACAACACUACUUACUGAUAGACCAAAAAACUACACCAGUAGGUUGAUUCAAUCAAGAUGUAUGUAGACCUAAAACUACACCAAUAGGCUGAUUCAAUCAAGAUCCGUGCUCGCAGUGGGCUGAUUCAAUCAAGAUGUAUGUUUGCUAUGUUCUAAGUCCACCUUCUAUCCCAUUCAUGUUAGAUCGUUGAAACCCUGUAUCCCUCUGAAACACUGGAAGAGCUAGUAAAUUGUAAAUGAAGUAAUACUGUGUUCCUCUUGACUGUUAUUUUUCUUAGUAGGGGGCCUUUGGAAGGCACUGUGAAUUUGCUAUUUUGAUGUAGUGUUACAAGAUGGAAAAUUGAUUCCUCUGACUUUGCUAUUGAUGUAGUGUGAUAGAAAAUUCACCCCUCUGAACUGGCUCCUUCCCAGUCAAGGUUAUCUGGUUUGAUUGUAUAAUUUGCACCAAGAAGUUAAAAUGUUUUAUGACUCUCUGUUCUGCUGACAGGCAGAGAGUCACAUUGUGUAAUUUAAUUUCAGUCAGUCAAUAGAUGGCAUCCCUCAUCAGGGUUGCCAGAUGGUGAUAACAGUGUAAGGCCUUGGGUCUAAGGCAUCCACGACUGGAAGGGACUACUGAUGUUCUGUGAUACAUCAGGUUUCAGCACACAACUUACAUUUCUUUGCCUCCAAAUUGAGGCAUUUAUUAUGAUGUUCAUACUUUCCCUCUUGUUUGAAAGUUUCUAAUUAUUAAAUGGUGUCGGAAUUGUUGUAUUUUCCUUAGGAAUUCAGUGGAACUUAUCUUCAUUAAAUUUAGCUGGUACCAGGUUGAUAUGACUUGUCAAUAUUAUGGUCAACUUUAAGUCUUAGUUUUCGUUUGUGCCUUUGAUUAAUAAGUAUAACUCUUAUACAAUAAAUACUGCUUUCCUCUAAAAAGAUCGUGUUUAAAUUAACUUGUAGAAAAUCUGCUGGAAUGGUUGUUGUUUUCCACUGAGAAAGCUAAGCCCUACAUUUCUAUUCAGAGUACUGUUUUUAGAUGUGAAAUAUAAGCCUGCGGCCUUAACUCUGUAUUAAAAAAAAUGUUUUUGUUUAAAAAAAACUGUUCCCAUAGGUGCAGCAAACCACCAUGGCACAUGUAUACCUAUGUAACAAACCUGCACAUUCUGCACAUGUAUCCCAGAACUUAAUGUAAACAAAAAAAUCUUAAAGUGCAAAUAUUAAAAAAAACUGUUCUCUGUGAAAAAAAUUAUAUUCCAUGUUAUAAAGUAGCAUAUGACUAGUGUUCUCCUAGAGAUCAGACUUUUUUGAUUGUAUAGUUUGCAUUAAAAAGUUGUACAGGGAGGGAUGUAACCUGUAUCUUCAGGAUAAUAGGGAAAUUAAUAAGGAAAAUAAUAAUUACUAAAAUUUGAGUUGAAGUCAGGGAAUUAUUUCUUUGGUUUUGAGUCUCUUUAUACAUCCAUUAGUAGAACCUGUCUAGUCUGAUUGCCACAGUCCUUGAAUUGAUGGUAAGGGGGAGUCAGUUACAGUUAGAAAAAAACCUGGGCAAAAACUACUAGUUAAAUGAUCAUGAAUUUUGAGUAUGUGUUUUAAAAUGCUUGGAGUUAUUGCAGAAAAAUGAUAUUCUCCAUUAGAACAUUUGAUGUGUGACUUUUGACAUAGGAUAAGGUGAUAAGAAAAUUAAGUUGAAAAAUAGUGACUCAAGUACAGCAAAUCAGAUUUUUGGCUACUGAGAUUAAAGAAGCAAAUAUUUAAAGGAUUAUCAGCAAUUUUCAAAUACAUAUUUUUCACUGCAGUGGUUUUGAAGAAUGUUUUAAGGUUAUAUUUAGAGUUUUUAAAAAAGUUUUCCCUCAGCCAGCCAUGGUGGCUCACAUCUGUAAUCCCAGCACUUUGAGAGGCUGAGGCGGGCGGAUCACCUGAGGUCAGGAGUUCUAGACCAGCCUGGCCAACAUGGUAAAACACCGUCUCUAAUAAAAAUGCAAAAAUUAGCUGGGUGUGGUGGCAAGCACCUGUAAUCCCAGCUACUUGGGAGACUGAGGCAGGAGAAUCACUUGAAUCCAGGAGUCAGAGGUUGCAGUGAGCCGAGAUCACACCACUGCACUCCAGCCUGGGCGAUAAGAGUGAACCUGCAUCUCAGAAAAAAAAAAAAAGUUUUCCCUCAUUAUUAAAAAGGAAAAAUUAUAGAAAAUUAAAAUAUAGAAUGUAGAAAGAGGAAAAACACCACACAUCACUCGUCAGGUGGAUUGGUUUGUUUAUUUUUAAGAUGGGUUUAUUUUGGAUAGCCAGUUAGAAAACGCCCUUAUAGCUGAUGUGUGCUUGUGCAUACUGAAUUGUAUACUUAAUUCUGAAAGUAAUGAGGAAACAUUUCACCUAAUGAUAACUGGUACAAAGGAAAGUUCACGUGUCUUUAAUAGUUUGCUAAUUAGACUAGCUGGUUAGAAAGAGGGAUCACUAGAUUGGAGAGAGAGAUCCAGUUUCCACUGGAGGCAGUAGGUCUGCUCAUUUCCAUGGUGACAAUCCUAAUGGCAGAGGGAGUGAGUUUCCCUUAGUGGCACAGGCUGGGGGUUUUGAGCUUUUAAGUUUUGUUUUAUAGAAAUCUGGAGAAUUUUACAUUUUACUUCACUAUAUAUCUAUGUUUAAAAUAAUUCAUUUUUGAUGUCCCAAAAUUGAUGUGGGUUGCCUUAUUUCCAGGCACCAGGUUGCUCACUGCAAGGUGACAUUUUGAGAAGCAGAAAUCUCUAGGUAUAUCUUAAGUGUGAAAAGCUUGUUAGAUUUCCAUGGCCUAUUCCAGGUGGGUUGUUGGGUUUAUGUUGUAAGCAUCAAACUUUUGUGGAAAUAAAUACCUAAUACAAGGUA